GUGCGUACGCUGGAAAACCGCUGGGGUGCGCGAUUCCGCACGGGGGCGCACAUGCGCAGUCUGGGGCCACGGUAAAAGAAAAUUACGAGAAUACAUUUAGCGUGUUACCUACGUUUUAGAGGCGCGUAGCAAGAGCUUCUCUGAAAGACUGGCAGUAUAGUAGUAGUCAGUGAUAAUAUUGAGCCUUAAUAUGUUCCAGACACUGUCCUAAGUGAUUUACCUUACAUUAUUCCCCUGAAUGUUUAUAAUUCCCAAGUGAAAGAAGGAAAUGAUAUAUUGGAUAGCUAUGAGUGGGGAGGUUUGUACUGGCUGCUUUCCCAUAAAGAAAUUAAGCACGUUCACGAAGGGCACGUAGUUUGUUAGUGUCUGGAACCCAGUUUUCGUGCCUGAAGUUCAAAUGUUCUUGCUACACCACCAUAGAAACUAACGUCACUCAGGAACCAUUUGUCAGGGCAAAGGGUGCCACCAUUUUGCAUUUCCUCCUGCCUUAGGACCAUCCUAAAUCACUCGCAUGGAGUGUUUUGGAAGAACUCUCAAGAGCUUCGUUUGCCUAGAGUCAGAAUUCCUAACCUUGAGUCCUGGUUUUGCCACAAACCCAAGCCGUUUGAUCUUGGGCAACUCCCGAAGAAAGCUGGGUUCAACUUCCUCACUGUCAAACUGGUUGUAGGUCUAGAUAAGUUUCAAGUACUCUUUUUAUGUGCAUGGUCUCUGACAUAGGAAGACUACAUACUGGGCCAGUAACAGGAAGGCACAAAGCUGACUGGAGGUUUAAAAAUUACUUGGUCAAUUUGAUUAAUGAGGAGAAUGAAUCAGAAAAUUUCAAGUUCUCCCGUGGCUAACUGUCGAGUAUCCACUUCAAGUUUUUAGCUUUUUUCUCAGGUCAGUCCACUGGACAUUUUCCAUGCCAAAUAGAAAUCCACAUUCAGCUGGAAUCAUUCCAUCGGAAAGAGGUCGAAAAUGUACAGUAGGCAUGCACAAAGGAUACCGCCUGGAAAGAAGGUAAAACUGGAAAACAGGAGGGAGGCGGGGCCCAAUUUUGGCUUCUCCUUCCGUCUCCGCCCCUCGAACGCCGGCCUGCGAGUGACGUCACGCGAGACUUGUACUUCCGCUUCCGGUAACUCACGUUUCUCUUUCUUCCUGUCUGCUUGGAAAGAUGGCGUCCCGCAAGGAAGGUACCGGCUCUACUGCCACCUCUUCCAGCUCCACCGCCGGCGCAGCAGGGAAAGGCAAAGGCAAAGGCGGCUCGGGAGAUUCAGCCGUGAAGCAAGUGCAGAUAGAUGGCCUUUCCAAUAUCAGAUGGAAAUGAUGCGGAGCCUUCGCCAUGUAAACAUUGAUCAUCUUCACGUGGGCUGGUAUCAGUCCACAUACUAUGGCUCAUUCGUUACCCGGGCACUCCUGGACUCUCAGUUUAGUUACCAGCAUGCCAUUGAAGAAUCUGUCGUUCUCAUUUAUGAUCCCAUAAAAACUGCCCAAGGAUCUCUCUCACUAAAGGCAUACAGACUGACUCCUAAACUGAUGGAAGUUUGUAAAGAAAAGGAUUUUUCCCCUGAAGCAUUGAAAAAAGCAAAUAUCACCUUUGAGUACAUGUUUGAAGAAGUGCCGAUUGUAAUUAAAAAUUCACAUCUGAUCAAUGUCCUAAUGUGGGAACUUGAAAAGAAGUCAGCUGUUGCAGAUAAACAUGAAUUGCUCAGCCUUGCCAGCAGCAAUCAUUUGGGGAAGAAUCUACAGUUGCUGAUGGACAGAGUGGAUGAAAUGAGCCAAGAUAUAGUUAAAUACAACACAUACAUGAGGAAUACUAGUAAACAACAGCAGCAGAAACAUCAGUAUCAGCAGCGUCGCCAGCAGGAGAAUAUGCAGCGCCAGAGCCGAGGAGAACCCCCGCUCCCUGAGGAGGACCUGUCCAAACUCUUCAAACCACCACAGCCGCCUGCCAGGAUGGACUCGCUGCUCAUUGCAGGCCAGAUAAACACUUACUGCCAGAACAUCAAGGAGUUCACUGCCCAAAACUUAGGCAAGCUCUUCAUGGCCCAGGCUCUUCAAGAAUACAACAACUAAGAAAAGGAAGUUUCCAGAAAAGAAGUUAACAUGAACUCUUGAAGUCACACCAGGGCAACUCUUGGAAGAAAUAUAUUUGCAUAUUGAAAAGCACAGAGGAUUUCUUUAGUGUCAUUGCCGAUUUUGGCUAUAACAGUGUCUUUCUAGCCAUAAUAAAAUAAAACAAAAUCUUGACUGCUUGCUCAUUUGAUUUUAGAUGUAUUUUCUCUGGCUUACUUUUGUUUGCUUAUACUUGUUUAUUUCUAAAAGCUAAAACAAGCCCUGACCGGAAGUUUCACCAGGCAGAAACCUAUAGGCUCCACCACUUUUGCUGCCUCUCAGGUGCCACCUUUCAACCCACUUCUCCCAACUACUUAUCCCAGCUCCUGACCCCGAGGCCCUGGCAUCUACUGUGAAUAUUUUUUUUUUGAAUUUUUAUACUUCGCUGCUCCCAAAUGAGCACCCCGAGAGAAGUCCAGGCUUCAUGUACUUGCCCAGGAAUUCCUUGUCCCCGGACCCGGAAUCACUUGGCCUAAUUCCGGUCAGUCUGCCUUUUCAUUUCUGCAGGUGAUGGUCAACCAGUCCCCGUACUCAUAGGCCAUGGGACACAAGAUUAUUAUUAUCAUCAUUAUUUUUAAAGACAGAGUCUCACUUUGUUGCCCAGGCUGGAGUGUAGUGGCACAAUCUCAGCUCGCUGCAACCUCCACCUUCUGAGUUCAAGCGAUUCUCCCACCUCAGCCUCCCAAGUAGCUGGGACUACAGGCGUGUGCCAUCACGCCUGGCUAAUUUUUGUAUUUUUAGUAGAGAUGGGGUUUCACCAUGUUGGCCAGGCUGGUCUGCAUCUCCUGACCUCAAGUGAUUCACCUGCUUCUGUCUCCCAAAGUGCUGGGAAUACAGGCAUGAGCCACCACUCCUGGACAGGCCACAGAAAUUUUAAAGAAAAGAAUCAUGCCACCACAAGUAAACUUCAUUUUGUUUAUAUUAUUUAGGACUUCACAUUUGUCUUCCGAAACCAUGAAGUAUAAUUCUGCUAACAGCAAGUGUUGUGAAUGAGGAAUUAGGAAUUAGGAGAAUGGUAGUACAUUGGGAAAAACAUAUUUUAGUAAUUUUUAUAUUUUAAAGAUAAUCACAGAUUUUGCUGUUUGUGCAUCACCAAAAUCAGUGAGAUCUGCCAGCUGGUGGGGGUGUGCCUAUGAGAAUUUUUGAUUAUGAUCCCCUAGGAGGGUUAUCAAAAAAGGAGAUGGGUGAAAGAUCAGGAGAGUCGAGAAAUUCAUUUUUUGGACAACAUUGUUUUGAAGGCACUACUGGGGCUCUGGGAUCAGGCAGCCAGAUUGAAACCUGGCUCCUCCUUUUCCUAAGUUAUUUAACCUCCCUGUGCCUCACUUUUUGUCAACCAGAUAAGAUAAGAAAUGAGAGCAGGUCUGUUACCUCACAAGGUGGCUGUGAGUGUUGAAGACGUUUGUUGGGGGUUUGGGUGAAGCAUGCAAACUCUGGUUGGUAUGUGGCAGCCACUCAGCCUGUAUUUAUGAUGAGGGAGGCAUUCUAGGCACCCCUUCCAGGAUGUUGGGUUGUUGGCUGGGUUUUACUUUAAAAAGCUCAGGGCCUAGAACAUUCUAGAAUCCAAGUACUUGCUCACAUAUAUAAUUAUUUCUUUAGGAUAAUCUUUGAUAUAGACUUACGAGUCAAAGGGUAUGUAAAAUGUCAGCCCUUUUACCUGUAUUGCCAAAUUGCCUUCAAAAGUUUCUGCUGUUUUGCCCUCCUACCCAUAGUGAUAACCUUAAAUUGGAGUCAACACAAAUUUGAGUGUGACUGUGUUAGACAGAAGGGAUAUAUUAACAGGUAAAACUGGCCAUGGCCCCUGCCCUUGUGGAGUAUAUGCUCUGUUGGUUCAUUUCCUCUGCAUUCUAAUUUUCUAGACUUGGGAUCUUAUUGUGGAGUUAAACAAAGCACCCUUAAAGUAGCAAGCGAGCAAAAUAAAAGCAAGGAAAAUCAGUUGGAACAUAACUUAUGUAUUUUUUAGGAUUAAGAGUAAUUUAACUGAGUCAAUUCAAUAUGUUUUUAAAGGUGUGAUUCUUAAAUUCUUUAUGAUUGUUUAGAUUUCUAUAUCUUGGUAACAUGAAUACACACUUAAUGAAAGAUUUCAGUAAUUUUUGAUUUGGGAAUUAAUCAUAGUGGGAAAAACUGUUUAGGAAAACAUGUCAGUGGAAAUUAACUCGCCACAGUAUGUAGUGUUAGGGAAUAGCUUCUGUUCGGCAUUUGAUUUGAGUGCUGUAUUCUGACAUUUUUCAGGAACAAAUACAUGUGAUUCAUCUUCUAUAAAUAUUUGCAGUUUCUUCAAGUUGAAAUGAGAAAAGCUCGUAAAUUGAGCACCAGGUCUAAUAAAUCAUUCACUUACCCAAGAACAGAAAGACAGGAAAAGCUAGCAUGUUAAUCUAAUGAAAAAAUCGAAUGUUAAAAAACCAAGAAAGUAGAAGAUAUUUGACAUUAACUUUCUAAUCAUUGAUAAUAAUCUAAUAAUCAUAACAUUAUUCUUAAAACCUGAAAGAAUGGAUUCCUGCUCCCAAUGUGUUUUUAAUAUCAACUUAAACUAAAAUAAUUUUUUUACCUAUUUUUGGAAGCUUGGAAAUUGAGAUGUAGUUGUCUAAUGUUAACCUAAUUAAGAGAGCUUGGUGUGAUUUCUCAUAUACAGCAUCUAAAUAUUUAAGUUUUAAUGUCUUCUAAAAUAUUAUUACAUUCUUCAUACUAUAGUUUUUUAACAUCCUUUAGAAAACUUGUAUCAGCUUCACUUUCAAACCAUGCUGGCAUCGAACUCAGGUGUAGUGGUAUCAGAAUGUUAUGAAAUAAUUUUUUAUUUUCAUUAUAAACUCCAUUUUUACAAUAAACACUUCUCAACCAAA